GGAGUCUCGCUUUCGCUCUGUGGCCCAGGCUGGAGUGCAAUGGCGCGAUCUCGGCUCACUGCAACCUCUGCCUCCCGGGUUCAAGCGAUUCUCCUGCCUCAGCCUCCACAGUAGUUGGGAUUACAGGAUCACGUGAUAAGGCACUAGCAGAUGUGGUUGGAAUCCUUGCUGUGCUGAAUCCUGGCUGUGUGACCCCAAGCUCCAGAUGGACCCUGGGAAGGACAAAGAGGGGGUGCCCCAGCCCUCAGGGCCGCCAGCAAGGAAGAAAUUUGUGAUACCCCUCGACGAGGAUGAGGUCCCUCCUGGAGUGGCCAAGCCCUUAUUCCGAUCUACACAGAGCCUUCCCACUGUGGACACCUCGGCCCAGGCGGCCCCUCAGACCUACGCCGAAUAUGCCAUCUCACAGCCUCUGGAAGGGGCUGGGGCCACGUGCCCCACAGGGUCAGAGCCCCUGGCAGGAGAGACGCCCAACCAGGCCCUGAAACCCGGGGCAAAAUCCAACAGCAUCAUUGUGAGCCCUCGGCAGAGGGGCAAUCCCGUACUGAAGUUCGUGCGCAAUGUGCCCUGGGAAUUUGGCGACGUAAUUCCCGACUAUGUGCUGGGCCAGAGCACCUGUGCCCUGUUCCUCAGCCUCCGCUACCACAACCUGCACCCAGACUACAUCCAUGGGCGGCUGCAGAGCCUGGGGAAGAACUUCGCCUUGCGGGUCCUGCUUGUCCAGGUGGAUGUGAAAGAUCCCCAGCAGGCCCUCAAGGAGCUGGCUAAGAUGUGUAUCCUGGCCGACUGCACAUUGAUCCUCGCCUGGAGCCCCGAGGAAGCUGGGCGGUACCUGGAGACCUACAAGGCCUAUGAGCAGAAACCAGCGGACCUCCUGAUGGAGAAGCUAGAGCAGGACUUCGUCUCCCGGGUGACUGAAUGUCUGACCACCGUGAAGUCAGUCAACAAAACGGACAGUCAGACCCUCCUGACCACAUUUGGAUCUCUGGAACAGCUCAUCGCCGCAUCAAGAGAAGAUCUGGCCUUAUGCCCAGGCCUGGGCCCUCAGAAAGCCCGGAGGCUGUUUGAUGUCCUGCACGAGCCCUUCUUGAAAGUACCCUGAUGACCCCAGCUGCCAAGGAAACCCCCAGUGUAAUAAUAAAUCGUCCUCCCAGGCCAGGCUCCUGCUGGCUGCGCUGGUGCAGUCUCUGGGGAGGGAUUCUGGGGGUGUCACCUUCUGGUGGCCCAGGUGGGCACCUUCAGCUUUCUUUAGUUCCUCAGUUUCCCGGGGGCAGACUACACAGGCUGCUGCUGCUGCUGCUUCCGCUUCUUGUCCCGGCCUGUGGGAGCCUCCUCCCCAGACUCUGAAUUCAGUGGCGGCCCUGGCAUCUCCUCUUGGGGCACUGUCUCUGGCAUCCGGCUUUCCUGACUCUGCUUCUUCCUCUUCUUGGUGGAUCCCGGAGUUGCCCUGGCUUCAGGCUGUCCCUCCCCUGGCAGUUCAGGCUCUAGUGGCUGAAUUGGCUCAGUCACUGUGUGACCUCUCUCUUUCUUCUUCUUCUUCUUCUUGGUGGAUGUGGGAGCUGCCUGAGGCUCAAGGUCAUCCGGCAGCUCAGGCCCCACCACCUCUGUCUCUGGCUCCACUGUGGCAUCUUGCUGUUUUUCUUUCUUCGUCUUCUUUUUGGGAGCUGCCAGAGCUGCCUGGGCCUGAGGCUUCGCUCCUUCUGGCUGUUGAGGCGCCAUGGUCCCCCCUGGGGACUCCAGAGGCUUCAUCUCCGGCUCCACUGGCUCCAUCGCCUCCGUCCCUGGCUCCAUCAUUGCCAUCUGUCCCUUUUCUUUUUUCCUCUUCUUCGUAGGGGGCAGAGGGAUGGCUUCCUCCAGUGGCUCCACCUUCACCUGUGGCUGAGACUCAACUGUCACCCCCUCCUCUGGCUCCAUCCCUUCCGUCCCCUUUUGCCUCUUUCUCUUUUUGGUCGGGGACAGGACUGUGUCUUCUAGAGGCUCAGUGUUAAUCUGUUCCUGCUUCACUGUCUUGUCUUCUGGCUCGAAGGUUUCUUUCCCUUUGGGCUUCUUCCUCUUCUUGGUGGUGGACGGGAACAGCACUCCCAGAGGCUCCAGUGUCUCCACUGUGGGCUCUGUCCCCACAGGCCCUGCUGCCUCUGGUUCUUUCAGCUGCUGAUUUUUUUUCUUCUUCUUCUUCCGCACAUCCAUUUCUGGCGACCCCAAAGCCAUGUCCACCUCCAGGGCCCCGUGCCCAUUCACUGCCUCCUGAGUGACUGGGGCCUCUGUCACCUGCAUCUCCUUUUUCUUCUUCCCUGAGGUGAGCAGGUUGGGGGCCAAGGCUGACCUAGGCCCUGUGACUGGUGGGUUGCCCCCAAAGGCACAGAACCGAGGCCUCAGGCCAGGAGGGAUCUGUGGUGGGGGACUUGCUGGGAUGGGCUGCAGAGGGCUCCCUGACAGGGAUUGCUGGGGACCCUCAAGGAUCCUUAGGGUGCCCUGGGGGGCUGAGGCACAGGUGAGUCCACCUCCUGCCUCCGUUGAGGGGGCCAGCAGGGUCGCUUCUCCAGCUUGGGGACAGCUGCUGAGGACUCGAUAGCGGUGCCGCUUGCCUGCCAAUUUGCCCUUGACGAUCUGGGAGCCAGAGAGAGGCACAUGCCGCCCAUUGAAGCUACAGAGAGAAACAGGGAGGGCAGAGGCUUAAGUGGAACAGGAGAGGGAAGGUUUUUUGAUUUUUUUUUUGUUUUUUUUUGAGAGAGUCUUGCUCUGUUGCCUAGGCUGGAGUGCAGUGGCAUGAUCUCGGCUCACUGCAAUGUCCACCUCCUGGGUUCAAGCGAUUCUCCUGCCUCAGCCUCUCAAGUAGCUGGGAUUACAGGCACCUGCCACCACGCCCAGCCAAUUUUUGUAUUUUUAGUAGAGACAAUUUCACUAUGUUGGCCAGGCUGGUCUUGAACUCCUGACCUCAAGUGAUCUGCUCGCCUCGGCCUCCCAAAGGAUGGGAUUACAGGCACCAGCCACUGCGCCUGGCUGGCCUCUGGUUUUUAAUAAAACAUGACUAGAGUGACUCCAUCUUAAAGUGAGUAGCUAGGCACUUACAAGGUUCAUGCUUAUGGCCUGAAAAUAACCACAUCCCAGGCUGACCACCAAUUAUAAUUACAGAAUAUUUAUGGCCAUACAGAACAUGUUCCACCAAGCCUGCAGAAUGUCCAAAUGUCCUAAGAAUGCAGCCCCCAUUACUUAAAUAUAACAUAAAUGAGCAAGCUUAGGUUGCAGGAUUAAUGGUCGUGGAUAACACCAAUAGCCCCUACCUUUAGUGAGCUUAUCUGCACACUCCAAGUUUAACUAUAGUUCCUUAUAGUUUCUUAUAAGUAGAAAUACUAACAAAGGGCUGUGGGUUUCUCCCCCUGCUUUCUGAGGACACUCUACUCUGUAAAGGAGUAGUUUCCAAUAAACUUGUUUCUUUCACUGUG